UCAAGACCAGGCAGGCAUAGUGUCCAGUAGCCAGCAAGAGCAGCCAGGCCCCAUCUAAAGGAAGCUAGGCUGCCCAGCUUCAGGCAAGUGUUGGCAUGCAGGAACAUAGGUCAUUGUGGCCAGAUCGCUCAUUCUUCAAGAAAAGCCGUGAAAUCUAGAUUGUAUGAGAAAGCUCCUAAUUUUUAAGACAACUUAUUUUAAAAAAUUAAACAUCUGUCUGCAGUCCAGAUGGAUAAAGAGACAUCCCUGUGGUUGGAGGACUACACCAAGGAGGUGGGGCUCAUGCCAGGCCUUGAAUGACGCUGUUGGCAUUGCUGAUCUUGGUGCUGUACUUGAGCACAGAGAUAUGGGGAAGCAGUUGGGAGGUGUCAGAAAGGAUCAGAGAAUGUAACUACUACCAGAAUCUUGCAGUUCCCCAGGGGCUUGAAUAUCAGACCAACGAGCCCUCAGAAGAACCGAUAAAGACCAUCAGGAACUGGCUGAAGGAGAAGUUGCAUGUCUUCUCGGAGAAGUUAGAGGAAGAGGUGCAGCAGCUGGAGCAGCUAGCGUGGGACCUGGAACUGUGGCUGGAUGCUCUUCUGGGAGAGCCACACCAGGAGGAGCACUGCUCCACAUAUAAAAGUCACUUGUGGGAGUGGGCCUGGGCCCUGGGGAGAGAGCACAAAGGUGGGGAGGGGUUGCUAGAGAUUUCUCUAAGCGGGGCAGAGCUCUGACUCUUGAAGUUCCAGUCAGGCAAGAAAAUAAAGUAGUUGGGAAAUGAA